AGGACGCCGCCCGGCGCGGAGUGGCUGCCCUGCGCGGGGACACUUAGAGCCCGGUGGGCGGGAGGAAGGCGGCAUGCCCCAGACGGUGAUCCUCCCGGGCCCUGCGCCCUGGGGCUUCAGGCUCUCAGGGGGCAUAGACUUCAACCAGCCUUUGGUCAUCACCAGGAUUACACCAGGAAGCAAGGCGGCAGCUGCCAACCUGUGUCCUGGAGAUGUCAUCCUGGCUAUUGACGGCUUUGGGACAGAGUCCAUGACUCAUGCUGAUGCGCAGGACAGGAUUAAAGCAGCAGCUCACCAGCUGUGUCUCAAAAUUGACAGGGGAGAAACUCACUUAUGGUCUCCACAAGUAUCUGAAGAUGGGAAAGCCCAUCCUUUCAAAAUCAACUUAGAAUCAGAACCACAGGACGGGAACUACUUUGAACACAAGCAUAAUAUUCGGCCCAAACCUUUCGUGAUCCCGGGCCGAAGCAGUGGAUGCAGCACUCCCUCCGGGAUUGACUGUGGCAGUGGACGCAGCACCCCUUCUUCUGUCAGUACUGUUAGUACCAUUUGCCCAGGUGACUUGAAAGUUGCGGCUAAGCUGGCCCCUAACAUUCCUUUGGAAAUGGAACUUCCUGGUGUGAAGAUUGUACAUGCUCAGUUUAAUACACCUAUGCAGUUGUACUCAGAUGACAAUAUUAUGGAAACACUCCAGGGUCAGGUUUCAACAGCCCUAGGGGAAACACCUUUGAUGAGCGAGCCCACAGCCUCGGUGCCCCCCGAGUCGGACGUGUACCGGAUGCUCCACGACAAUCGGAAUGAGCCCACACAGCCUCGCCAGUCGGGCUCCUUCAGAGUGCUCCAGGGAAUGGUGGACGAUGGCUCUGAUGACCGUCCGGCUGGAACGCGGAGUGUGAGAGCUCCGGUGACGAAAGUCCAUGGCGGUUCAGGCGGGGCACAGAGGAUGCCGCUCUGUGACAAAUGUGGGAGUGGCAUAGUCGGUGCUGUGGUGAAGGCGCGGGAUAAGUACCGGCACCCUGAGUGCUUCGUGUGUGCCGACUGCAACCUCAACCUCAAGCAAAAGGGCUACUUCUUCAUAGAAGGGGAGCUGUACUGCGAAACCCACGCAAGAGCCCGCACAAAGCCCCCAGAGGGCUAUGACACGGUCACUCUGUAUCCCAAAGCUUAAGUCUCUGCAGGCGUGGCACGCACGCACGCACCCACCCACGCGCACUUACACGAGAAGACAUUCAUGGCUUUGGGCAGAAGGAUUGUGCAGAUUGUCAACUCCAAAUCUAAAGUCAAGGCUUUAGACCUUUAUCCUAUUGUUUAUUGAGGAAAAGGAAUGGGAGGCAAAUGCCUGCUAUGUGAAAAAAACAUACACUUAGCUAUGUUUUGCAACUCUUUUUGGGGCUAGCAAUAAUGAUAUUUAAAGCAAUAAUUUUUUGUAUGUCAUACUCCACAAUUUACAUGUAUAUUACAGCCAUCAAACACAUAAACAUCAAGAUAUUUGAAGGACUCUAAUUGUCUUUCCUUGACAAGUUGAUUUUGCAAUUGUGGUAAAUAGCAAAUAACAAUCUUGUAUUCUAACAUAAUCUGCAGUUGUCUGUAUGUGUUUUAACUAUUACAGUGCAUGUUAGGGAGAAAUUCCCUGAAUUUCUUUAGUUUUGUAUUCAAACAAUUAUGCCACUCGAUGCAACAAACAUAAUAAAUACAUAAAAGAUUUAAAAAAUACCUAAUGAAGUGGCAUUCAUUGAAUUCAAAUAAAAUCAACAUUUCAAUGAGAGAACCCAAUCAUAUUUUAACAUGUACACUAACAAAUAUUUUAAGAUAAAUGUGGCUUCUUCAGGUUUUAUAACUCAUUACUCUUUCUUAUGAGCACAAAAUUUCUGAUGAUAGAAGCGUUGAAAUUUGCUAGUUAAAGGUAGUUCAGUCUCUUUCAAAUUAAAAGUUUCACUUGCUUCAACAGAGACUCUUUCAAUUUAAAUAUCUCUUUCAGAUCAAUAUUCAGUCAAAUUGAAGGUUCAAAGUCCAUCACUGCUGUUUCUUAGGCUCAAUGGUUCACCACCUCCUCCUCUUCCCAAGAUGGCAUCUCCAGGAAGAAACAAUUUAGACGACUUCCUAAGGAAGGCAGGGGCUGCUGGUCUCCUGGGGUCCUGCUUGUAUCCACUGUUGAAAUCCUUGGUUUCACUUGUGAUCUGUGGUCUGUUUUCUUGACAUAGUUGAGGCCAGGCAAUAAUAACACCUCCACUACCACCUCCAAAACUCUCAGCUCAGCUUUCCUGGAGUCAUGGAUCCUCUGUCUGAGACAUGCACUCUGCCUGGCCCUGGCGCAGGCAGCCUACCUUGCAGGCUCUGCAUGGCGUUACCUUGCCUCUCACCCAGGGUGCCCAUGGCAAUGCUCCUGACUUGCAUCUCUCACCUACUUUCCAUGUCCCCCACUGGGGACGUACAGGAACUUCUGAAACUGUCCCCUCAGGUUCAAACCAUGGGGAACCAGCAGGGUGGGGACCCUCAGACCCUCUGUCUCACCACCUUGUGUCACAUGGUCAUCUCUACCACCCCUCAACCCCCACAGCUGCUAACUUCUGGCCUGAAACAAGUGUUCUCCUCCCAUAAGGUCCCAAAUGGGACACAAGUUUUAUUGCUCUGGGAUUCUUCCAAACUUAACUGACUCUGACCCUGACCUGUUCAGGAUUUUGAGAGGAGCCAAAACACGUGCCUGGCCCCUGUAGGCAUUUGACAUUGCAACUCCUGUGCCAACACAUGCAUUCACUAACAAAGCUAUUAAAAAAAUAAAACAGACUUUUGAGAUCAAAGAAA